GCUCUGGGGCUAUCAGGCCAGCAUGGACGCUGGCAAAGCGGGGCAGACCCUGAAGACUCACUGCUCAGCCCAGGUGAGAGCCUUCUGAGCUGUGCCUGGGGCUGGGGGGACAGGGCCCUGGAACCCCAGCAGCCGGCGGGUCUGGGAGCUGCUGUCCUUGAGUUGGUUGGGCCCUGGGAAGCUGGGUUCUGGCAGCCUGGUCCCUGAAUGGGUCCAGCCUGUACAGCUGGGGUCCCAGGUGGGGGUGGGACAGGAGCCAUGAGAUCUGAGUCCCAAGAAUGGGGGCUGGGCUGGGUUUCGGCUCAGUAGCUCCCCACUCCCCAAAGCGCCCAGAUGUCUGCAGGUGGCUGAGCCCCUUCAUCCUCUCCUGCUGCGUGUACUUCUGCCUCUGGAUUCCCGAGGACCAGCUGUCCUGGUUCGCUGCCCUGGUCAAGUGCCUGCCCGUCCUCUGCCUGGCUGGGUUCCUGUGGGUCAUGUCCCCAAGCGGGGGCUACACCCAGCUCCUCCAGGGAGCCCUUGUGUGCUCGGCUGUGGGGGACGCUUGCCUCAUCUGGCCGGCAGCCUUCGUCCCUGGCAUGGCCGCCUUUGCCACCGCCCACCUCCUCUACGUCUGGGCCUUCGGCUUCUCUCCCCUGCAGCCCGGCCUGCUGCUGCUCAUCAUCCUGGCCCCUGGCCCCUACCUCAGCCUUGUGCUCCAGCACCUCGAGCCGGAUAUGGUCCUGCCGGUGGCAGCCUAUGGGCUGAUCCUGAUGGCCAUGCUGUGGCGCGGCCUGGCCCAGGGCGGGAGUGCCGGCUGGGGCGCGCUGCUCUUCACGCUCUCUGAUGGCGUGCUGGCCUGGGACACCUUCGCCCAGCCCCUGCCCCAUGCCCACCUGGUGAUCAUGACCACCUACUAUGCUGCCCAGCUCCUCAUCACACUGUCAGCCCUCAGGAGCCCGGUGCCCAAGACUGACUGACUAGGGAGCUUGAAGGGCCGGUGUUCAGGCCCUCUCCUCCUGCAAGGACCUGGGCCUCCCAGCCCAGCCCAGCCUGAGAAAUACCCUCAGCAGCGAAGCUUCCUGACGCCUGUCUGCAGGCGCCGCUGCCGCCGUCGCUUCUGGCUGAAGACGUUUGAGGACGAUUUGCGGAAUUCCAAGUCCACUACUGGGUUCCAGCUGCCUUCCCCCGGUUCUGACUCCAGAUCCCUGGCUCCUCAGCCAGGCCCACAUGGAGCCCUCCCAGCCACCAGCCUGCCUCCAUGUUCACUGUCGGCCCCACAGCCUGCCCGCCCCCUGCUGCUGCUCUGAAUCCGUUUUCCCUGUGGGUGUGGAACCGUAGAUGUUGCUGUUACCGUAGGAGAGGCCUCGGGGAGGGUCAUGAUUGUGAUAAACCAUCGCGGUUAAUGACAGCAGAAGGUUCUUUGUCGCUCCCCAUGGACCAGGCCUGGUGCCCAGUGGGACCCUCCAUGGCCCUCUGGUGGGGGGAUUCGGGGGGAUAAAGUGAGGAUUGUGCAGAACUGA